GCAUGGUGCACGUACUACACUGCUGAUGUCGUGUACUUAGAAGAUGUGCGCUCAUAGCCCUUUCCCUCCAAAGAAAGCACCUGGACUACAACUUGAUUGAGGCCUCGCCAAUUUGUGAGACUAGAACAAAUAAGAUAAAGUAUAUGAGAGUUCUUUUUAUAAUAAACAUAGGGUGUUCAUAUUAGGAAUGACGUACAAGGUGGACUCCUGGGAAAAACAUCUACGCUCCCUUCUCCCUUGCCCUUCUCUCAAAAAGCAGGUACAUCUGUGUUUGGAACUUUUAAGUCCUAAGAGCAACUCUGGGGUGUUUAUGAGGGAAUGAGUGGAAUGUGGGGAAUACUAGACUCCCACGUCUUUAUUGCUACCAGAUGAAGCUAGGCCAGCAAAAGGUGGUGCUUACCUUAUGACUCUUAAAUUGGGAUGGGAUUGGAGCAGGGGAGGUGCACUUUCCUCAGAUUUGGCUUUUUCUAACUUGCGAAUGUCACUCAGAAAAGUUGUUCAUUUAUGAGUUCCACAAAAUUUGUUAGUCAUCAAAUAAUAGAGUUUUUCUUAAGUGACCACUUACAUACUCAUCUACAAUAAACCCCAACUAACUAAUUUUUCACUUUGUGUACCUCAUGCUAAUAUCCGUGGACAGUAAUGUGCCUGUUGUGUUCCUUUUGCUUUUCAUCCUUGUGAUCUUAUGUCACAUGGAAUGUAAAGGCCACAUAUAUAUAUGUGUGUGUGUGUGUGUGUAUAUGUAUAUUUUUAAGAAUAUUUAGUCUGGAUUUCAUGAAAUUGACUUCUGAAAUAAUUUGCCUCAAUUUUGUUUCCUGGUGGUUUGAGAAGAAAGUUCCUGUGGUGAAAUUGAAAAGGGGAUAAAGGGAAGUACUUAUUUUAAAACAUAAGUAACUUGUGGAUUGUUGAAUACUGGAAAAAGAGUGUUACUUCCCCGUUAACCUACGCCUCGUGUAAUCCUUCAGGUUGGAAGUCGGAUCGCAGACCGUGUAUAUGACAUACCCAGAAAUUUCCCCCUUGCUUUGGAUCUUGGUUGUGGAAGAGGUUACAUUGCACAAUAUUUGAAUAAGCUUCAGUUAUUCCAUUGCAGGAAACUAUUGGAAAGUUUUUCCAAGCUGACAUUGCAGAAAAUGCUUUGAAAAAUUCCUCAGAAACAGAAAUACCUACUGUCAGCGUUUUAGCUGAUGAAGAAUUCCUUCCCUUCAAAGAAAAUACAUUUGACCUGGUGGUUAGCAGUUUAAGUUUGCAUUGGGUGAAUGACCUUCCUAGAGCACUUGAGCAGAUUCAUUAUAUUUUAAAACCAGAUGGAGUGUUUAUCGGUGCAAUGUUUGGAGGCGACACACUCUAUGAACUUCGGUGUUCCUUACAGUUAGCGGAAACGGAAAGGGAAGGAGGAUUUUCUCCACACAUUUCUCCUUUCACUGCUGUCAAUGACCUGGGACAUCUGCUUGGGAGAGCUGGCUUUAAUACUCUGACUGUGGACACUGAUGAAAUUCAAGUUAACUAUCCUGGAAUGUUUGAAUUGAUGGAAGAUUUACAAGGUAUGGGUGAGAGUAACUGUGCUUGGAAUAGAAAAGCCCUGCUGCAUCGAGACACAAUGCUGGCAGCUGCGGCAGUGUACAGAGAAAUGUACAGAAAUGAAGAUGGUUCAGUACCUGCUACAUACCAGAUCUAUUACAUGAUAGGAUGGAAAUAUCAUGAGUCACAGGCAAGACCAGCUGAAAGAGGUUCCGCAACUGUGUCAUUUGGAGAGCUAGGAAAAAUAAACAACCUUAUGCCACCGGGGAAAAAAUCACAAUAAAUAUUUAUUCAGUGUUAAUGUCGUCCAGAAUUUUCAUCAGAAAUGGAUAGCUUUAACAUCUAAAAUUAUUAUAUUUUGAAGCAAGAAGCACUCUAAGCUAUUUACUAAUAGGCUUUUCAUAUAAUUAGGAAAACCUAAUAUCACAUCUAUAGUAACCAUUUCAGUUUCAUAUUGUUUCUGUUCUCAUAAGGAUACUGCUGAGUGUCUUUGCAGAUUCAGCCUAAAAGCAAAGAAAAUAUUUCCCUAAAAUAUUUGCAAAUAAUGUUCACAUAUGUAAAUGCCUUGGAAAAUAUUACUCAUGCUGACCUUUUACACCUUUUUCAUUUGUCAUACUGUUUUCUUUGCCUUGAAGAGGAACAGAUGAAUAUGCACCUUCUCCAGAGUUAUGUGGUUUUAGAAUUUAGAAGAGCAUGUAUCUUUAUUAAAUCCCUCCUCAACUCUUUUUUUUUAAAGCAUCUGAAUUUAACCUUAUUUCUUUUUUAUCUCCAUGGUGUGGGUGGGACCACCAUGGUUUUACACCCCACCCUACCUUAGGGAAGAAGAAAACAUUUUAAAGAAUACCAGAAGUAGAAUCACAUGUAACAGUCUCUGCACAGUCAUCAGUUUAUUGUUAAGCUUUCCUUUGUAAUUUCAGGGCUUAAGCACUAUUAUCCUAAUCCAAGUUCACAGUCCUGUUGUUGUCGAGGAGGGUUCAAAAUCAUUUGGAGAUAAUCAAGCUCAGACAGCUUAGGAUAGGUGAGAAGAACAUAGAGGAAGCAGGGAGAAGGCUGAGAAGCAAGCAGGAGUGAGCGCUAAGUGUUUUGUUUCCAGUUAGCUGUUCGCUGUCUUUUCCAUUUAACCUGGGCACUGCCCUAGCCUCAUCUUCAGCCUUCAGUGAUCUAUAAUAGCAUUUCCUUCUGUCUCCUCUCAGUCUCUCUUCUGCCUUCCUUCCCUCCUUUACUGUAUUAGCAACAAGCUGUCCAUGGGUGGGGGCUGUGUGUUAGCCUGUACGUAGCACAUGGGACUUUCCACAUAGUAGAUAUUCAGUUACAUUUUGAACUAAUUAUAUAACAAACUUGCCCUUUGAAAGACUAAGUUAUAGUUAAAAACCAAGAUUUGUAGGAGAAAAAGAAAUUAUUGUUCCCUUCAGUUUGAAAAAUCAUCGAUAUUUGAAACUGGGAUACGCUUGGUAGCUUUUUUGUUUUAACACAAAGUAAACCUGUGAAGUAGAAUUUGGCGUUUUGUUUUUUGGGGUUUUUUUUUUUUUUAGCUUAAUUUUCAGAACUUGAAGAGAGAGAACAACAACAAAAAACAAACUGCGCUAGCCAGGUGCAAUGGCGCAUGCCUGUAGUCCCAGCUACUUGGGAGGCUGAGGCAGGCAGGAGUUCAAGGCUGCAGUGAGCUGUCUGUGCCACGGCACUCCAACCUGGGCAAAAGAGGAGACCUCAUCUAAAGAAAAAUCCACCAAAAACCCUGUGUUUUAAAGUGCAAACUGAUGAUGGAGGAAUGGGUAAAUUCCAGGGGUCUAUAUUUCCAAAAGGACAUGUGUUUUUGUGCACUAAUACUUGUUUUUGAAGAACACAUCUCAGUGUUAAGUGGCUGUUGCUGAGGAAGGGGACUGAGGAACUGGGUGUGUCUGUGUCAUUCUGUUUGAAUGUCUGUCAGGGGUAUAGAAACUAGGAGGGAGACUUGUACUUUUCACUUUUUAAACUUCCUGUAAAAUUUGAAUUUUCCAAGCAAGAAUAUUACUUUUGCUUAUUUAAUGUCAACGGAAUUAUAUGUGGAUGGUGGGGUGGAGCUAAGGAUUACUCUACUCUGGCUAUCCCAAAAAAAGCUCCAUUUGUUUAAAAAAAUUAAGUAAAUCAAACACAGCUAAUUGAGGACCCUUAUUGUUUAAUGUGAGUGAUUGUAGUGAAAACACUUAUUUUAGUGUGUAUAACACUAGUGAAAUUAUUUUUGUAGUUAAAUCUGCUGGAAGUGUGCUAUUAAGCUUUUAUUGUUUGGAGCCCUCAGGAAACUAAUUUUUCUGAAUAACCACAUUUUCCAAAUGAUUAAGAGCUCAUCCUUUUAAGCAAUGAAACUUUUAAAAGGUCUUUAUCAAAAAUUUUUCAUAAAUGUUACAUUCUUAAAUGGUAUAUGAUAAAUAAUCAUCUUUUUUGUUGGUUUAUUUUUUUAUUUUUUAUUUUAUUUUAUUUUUUGAGACGGAGUCUCGCUCUGUCUCCAGGCUGGAGUACAGUGGCGCAAUCUCGGCUCACUGCUGCCUCCGCUUCCUGGGUUCAAGUGAUUCUUCCUGCCUCAGCUUCCCAAGUAGCUGGGAUUACAGGCGCGUGCCACCACGCUGGCUAAUUUUUGUAUUUUUAAUAGAGAUGGGGUUUCACCAUGUUGGCCAGGAUGGUCUCAAUCUCUUGACCUUGUGAUCUGCCCACCUUGGCUUCCCAAAGUGCUGAGAUUACAGGUGUGAGCCACCAGGCCUGGCCAAUAACCAUUUCUUGAUAACCCCACAGAUAAUAUCAUAAACUCAAGUUGUCUGUAUUGCUUCUUCCCAGACUGGUCCCAAGAAUGCUGUGGUUGGUUUUGUGUCUUUUCCAGCACUUUUCUUACUUGCUGUCAGUUGUCAAUCUCAACACCUUGACCAAAAUGAACUUUCUUGAGUCAUUUCUUCUCUGUUUAGCUAUAAGAUUAGAAUUCAUACUGAAAGAUUUCUAGGACUUUUGUAUUAAGGUAGGAAAGAGGAACUAGGUUCUGGGAGAAAGACUCCUUUGGAAUAAAAUUCAUGAGCUUUAUUGGUUCCUUUAACAGAUCUUCAUUGAGUUUCAUGUGCCAGGCAUCCAACUAGUCUCUGCUUUUAUAGUUGUCAGUCUGACAGGGCUCUAGUAUGUGCACACCGUGACACCUGUUGGCUGCCAGGAGACUGUUUGGCUUAUUUCCUGGUUCUUAGCAAUAUUCCAGGUUGGCCUGGAGAAUUCCAAAGGUAAAUAUGAAAAUGUAUACCUACAAAAGAAUUUUUGCUUUAUAGGAAGAAUUUGUAGGAUUUAUUGAGAUGUAAGCUACCUAUAUACAUCAAGUAUGUGAUAUGAUUGUAAAAAGUUACAGAAGUGUGUGAGUCAUGAAGUACCUGUGAGGGAAGUUUAUAUAUUUUUUCAAACUCUUUUAGUACCAUUUUCAUCCACUAGGUGGAAGCAAUUACAGUAUGACCUGCAUUAAAGACAUGUACAGUUUUUUGGCCGGCUGCAGUGGCUCACACCUGUGAUCUCAACACUUUGGGAAGCUGAGACGGGAGGAUUGCUUGAGCCCAGGAGUUUGAGACCAGCUUGGGCAACGUGAUGAAACCCUGUCUCUACAAAUAAAAAAAAAAUUAGCCAGGCAUGGUGGCACAAGCCUGUGGUCCCAGCUACUCAGAAGGCUGAGGUGGGAGUAUUGAUCGAGCCCAGGAGGUCAAGGCUGCAGCAAGCUGUCGCACCACUGCACUCUAGCCUGGGCAACAGCAAGACCCUCGUCUCAAAAAAGAAAAAAAAAAAGUACAAUUUUUGUAUUGAUUAUGUAUUCCUUAAGUAGGAGUGGAAUAAAAGUAUUUUACCGUGGAUUGGCUUCUGUGAAGGAAAGAAGUGAAUAUUAGUAGAUAUUUGGAAAAAAGAAAGAUAGUUGAUGCAGUGAUUAUUAUUCUGUUCCUUUGUAAGUUACCAUUAGCCUCUCUUGCUUAAGAAAUAUUUUGAGCUUUUUUGGGGAGGGGUUGUGGUUAAUGAUGUGAAAUUAAUCUUCAGGAAAUUUAUCAUAAGCAGACUUGCCUUUUCAGAUAUUGGUAUAUUUUAAUUCUCUACCUGAAUACAUACAUGACAGUUAUUUUACCAUGCUGGUUUAAAAAACAUCAAUUUGAAAAUACUAGAAGGUGGGGUGAACACUGAUAAGUUACUGUUAACAAAUAAGAAAAUAAUGCUUUGCCAUCUGUGGUGGUUUUAAAAUCUAUCCACAAAUUUUUGAUAUGCUUCUCUUUAAGACGGGACACUUCAUUCCCCUCUAAGUACAGGCUGAGUUUAGUGAUUCCCUUCCAACAAAUAGAUGGUGUGUCACUUCUGAGACUAGGUAAUAAAAGGCAUUGCAUCCUCCUUACUCUCUCUUGGAUCCUUCACUCUAGGGAAAGCCAGCAGCCAUAUUGUAAGGCCACUCAACUCCAUGGAGAAGACCUAGAAGUGAGGAGCAGAGGCCUCCAGCCAAAAGCCAUGUGAGGGAGCCAUCUUGGAAGCAAUUCUCCAGGCCCAAACUUCAGAUGACUGUGGUCCCAGCCAAUGCAUUGACCACAACCUCAUGAGAGACCCUGAGCUAGAACCACCUAGCUAAGCCACUCUCAAAUAUCUUAUCUACAGAAACUGAGAUGAUAAAUGUUUGUGGUUUAA